AGAACUCUGUGGAUGAACCUUGAAGGAGCCUCCAAGCCUGAACCAAAGCACUACAGAUCACCUGCUAUCUUCAUAGCACCAUGAGUGAAGAAUCUGAUGGAAAGCUUAUUGAAGACAGCCUGAUUCAGCUGAGAUGUCACUUUACAUGGAAGUUGUUAAUUGAAGCCCCUGAAAUUCCUGAUUUAGAAAACAGGAUCUGGGAAGAGAUUCAGUUCCUGGACACCAAAUACAAUGUGGGAAUACACAACCUACUAGCCUAUGUGAAACACCUGAAAGGCCAGAAUGAGGAAGCCCUGGUCAGCUUGAAAAAGGCUGAAGACUUAAUUCAGAAAGAACAUGCCAACCAAGCAGAUAUUAGAAGUCUGGUGACCUGGGGCAACUUUGCCUGGGUGUAUUACCACAUGGGCAGAUUGGCAGAAGCCCAGACUUACCUGGACAAGGUGGAGAACACUUGCAAGAAGUUUGCAAAUCCUUCCCGCUAUAGAAUGGAGUGUCCAGAGGUGGACUGUGAGGAAGGAUGGGCCUUGGCGAAGUGUGGUGGAAAGAAUUAUGAACGGGCCAAGACCUGCUUUGAAAAGGCUCUGGAAGGGAACCCUGAAAACCCUGAAUUCAAUACUGGGUACGCAAUCACCGUCUAUCGCCUGGAUAAAUUUAACACAGCAUCAGGGAGGAAUAAGGCAUUUUCUCUGCACGUCCUAAAACGAGCUGUCAGGCUAAAUCCAGAUGAUGUAUAUAUUAGGGUUCUCCUUGCCCUGAAGCUUCAGGAUGAAGGACAGGAAGCUGAAGGAGAAAAGUACAUUGAAGAAGCUCUGACCAGUAUAUCUUCACAGGCCUAUGUCUUUCAAUAUGCAGCCAAGUUUUAUCGAAGAAAAGGGUCUGUGGAUAAAGCUCUUGAGCUCUUAAAAAUGGCCUUGGAGACAACACCCACUUCUGCCUUCCUGCAUCACCAAAUGGGGCUUUGCUACAGGGCACAAAUGAUCCAAAUCAAGGAAGCUACAAACUGGCAGCCUAGAGGGCAAGAUAGGGAAACUGUGGACAGAUUGGUUCAAUUGGCUAUAUGCAAAUUUGAAAAGACUAUAAUGUUAAAGCGAACAUUUGAGAUGGCCUAUGUUGACCUGGCUGAAACGUAUGCAGAAAUAGGCCACCACAGAAAGGCUGAGGAACAUUUUCAGAAAGGGUUACGCAUGAAGAUCUUUGAAGAUCAGCUAAAGCAAGAGAUUCAUUACCACUACGGCCGUUUCCAAGAACAUCAUGGGAAAUCUCAAGAUAAAGCAAUUACCCAUUAUUUAAAAGGUUUGAAAAUAGAAAAAAUGUCCCAUUCCAGGGAAAAACUUCUCAAUGCUUUAGAGAAAUUGGCUAAAAGAUGUAUUCACCAGAAUGUACGGGUUGUGGAAAGUGUCAGCCUCCUUGGGCUUAUCCACAAAUUGAAAGGAGAAGUAAGUGAUGCUUUGCUGUGCUAUGAGAGGGCUCUGAGGCUGGCUGCUGACCUGAACCCUAUAUUUUAACAUAGAGGUCACCAUUAUCCAUUUAAUGGUCUUAUAACUAAAUAGAAUGACUAUGAAAUUAAAUAAUGCAAACUUAAAGCUGUUGGAAAUUUACCUUAUUUUGAGCCUUGAGAGGAAUGUGGCUGUGUGGCCUGAGUUAUGUAGCAUGCAACUGCAACUUCUGCUUUUUCCUGUAAAUGAUCAGGAAAGGCCUUGUGGCACCAGACAUAAGACCCCCUGAAAGUAUCAUCCCUCCUGAUGGAAUGGUAAAGCAAUCUUUCUUGGAACAUAGCAAGUAGUAACCGAUCAAAUUGCUAUAACGUGUGUACUGACCUUAUGUGGAAAAUGCUGCAACCCUGUUUACUGCCUAUGUAAGUGAAAUCUUAACUUCCCCAUUUUGGAAUGCUGACUCCAGUCAUUAGGUGUCUGUAUUUCCUGAGUGGUUACCCUCAAGCUUUGUGCUCAAAUAAACUCUAUACUUAAUCAUA